AUGAGGGACGCGGAAGGGGGUGCUCAGCGCCCCGUCCCGCCGGCGGCCGCGAGACCAGAGCGAGCGAACGAACCGCGGCGGUCCGGAGAGCCCCGAGCGCAGCGCAGGACCUGGGUACGCCGCGAGGAACCGUGCAGCCCAGCGCGGCCGCCCGGCCCGGGUCCAGCAGCCAGGAGAGCGCAGCGCUUCGAAGCCGAGUGCGCGCCACCGCCCGCGCCCCGCGCUGGGGAAUGCGCCCUCGGCGCGCCGGCCAGGGGGCGCCCGCAGCCCACCCCAGGGGAGGCGGCCCCGAGCGCCCCUGAGCCUUCCCAUGGCCCGGGCUGGGGCCCGGGCCCUCGGCUGCUGACGCGCCCGAAGCCCGCGGAACCGGUUAAGCCGCGGCCGCGGCGCCGAUCCCGGCUGAGGCGCAGCGGCGAGAGGUCGCGGGCAGGGCCAUGGCCCCGGGGGGCCGCUAGCGCGGACCGGCCCAACGGGAGCCGCUCCGUGCCGCCGCCGCCGCCCGGGCGCCCAGGCCCCGCCGCUGCGGAAGAGGUGAGUGCAGCGGGAACCGGGAGGGAGCGGGCAGGCGGCCGGGCCACCCCGCGACCCCUCUGGGACCCGCGGCACUGCAACUCCGCAGAAGUGUCCGGGGAGCGGGUCUCGUCGAGCCGGGGGGCUGCCCGCGGACAUAGGGGCAACAAGGCUGGGGUGGGAUUCUUACCUGUCCUGGAGGCCCGGACCCCUUACCUACGGGGCGGCGUAUGGAUGUGUGGAUGA